ACCACUUUCUUUCCUUUUUUUUUUUUUUUUUUUUAAAUUAAGAGACAGGGUGUCUCAAUGUUGCCCAAGCUGGAGUUCAGUGGCUAGUGGCUAUUCACAAGAACGAUCAUCGCACACUACCUCAAACUCCUGGGAUCAAGCAAUCCUCCUGCCUCAGCUUUCCAAGUCGCUGGGACUAUAAGUGUGUACCACAGCAUGUCAGCUCUCUCUCUCCUUCUUGACCUAAAGCCUAGCAUAAAAUUAGCUAAGUAGAAUGUUUCCAAAGAUGGCUGCAUCAGUAUCUCCCAUCCCACAUAAUUUCUGUUUGAUUUUGCCAUUCACCCAUAAAAUGGUGGGAUCUACCUCCCCUCCUUGCAAAUUUGAGCUGGCCCUCUGAUCCUGUCUAAGAUCUGAAGCCAGAUAUUAAGGUACUUCAUUAAUUUCCAUGUUUGUCCUCUAUGCAACCUAGCAAUCAAGCAAGAAGUCAAAACAUACUGACAUAGUUUGGAUGGGUCCCCACCCAAAUCUCACCUUGCAUUGUAAUAAUUCCCACGUGUCAAGGGUGGGGCCGGGUGCAGAUAACUGAAUCAUGGGGAUGGUUCCCCCCAUACUGUUCUCGCGGUAGUGACUAAGUCUCAUGAGAUCUGAUGGUUUUAUAAAUGGGAGCUCCCCUGCACAUGCUCUCUCCUGCCUGCCACUAUGUGAGACAUGCUUUUGCACCUCCUUGCCUUCCACCAUGAUUGUGAGGCCUCCCCAGCCAUGCAGAACUGUGAGUCAAUUCAACCUCUUUCCUUUAUAAAUUACCCAGUCUCAGGUAUGUCUUUAUUUGCGGUGUGAGAACAGACUAAUACAAUAAGUUGAUACCAGUAGAGUGGGGUGCUGCUGUAAAGAUACCCGAAAAUGUGGAAGCAACUUUGGAAAUGGGUAACAGGGAGAGGCUGGAACAGUUUGGAAGGCUCAGAAGAGGAUAGGAAAAUGUGGGAAAGUUUGGAACUUCCUAGAGACUUGUUGAAUGGCUUUGACCAAAAUGUUAAUAGUGAUAUGGACAACAAGGUCCAGGCGGAGGUGGUCUCAGAGGGAGAUGAGGAAUUUGUUGGGAAAUGGAGUAAAGUCACUCUUACUAUGCAAAGACACUGCAGGCAUUGUGCACCUGUAUUAGAAACGGGCAUAAGAUAGGCGGGAAAGAGGGAAAAUAAGAAUUUCUUUCUAGAGUUCCCUACAGAUCUGUGGAACUUUGAACUUGAGAGAGAUGAUUUAAGGUAUCUGACAGAAGAAAUUUCUAAGCAGCAAAGCAUUCGAGAAGAAGCAGAGCAUAAAAGUUCAGAAAAUUUGUAGCCUGAUGAUGCAACAGAAAAGAAAAAUCUAUUUUCUCAGGAGACUGGGUUGUAGAAAUUUGCAUAAGUAAUGAGGAGCCAAAUGUUAAUCACCAAGACAAUGGGGCAAAUGUCUCCAGGGCAUGUUAGAGACCCUCACAGCAGACCCUCCCAUCACAGGCCAGGAGGCUUAGAAGGAAAAAUGGUUUUGUGGGUCCAGAACCCCCUGCUGUGUGCAGCCUAGGAACUUGGGGCCCUGCAUCCCAGCUGCUCCUGCCAUAGGUAAAAGGGGCCAAGGUACACCUCAGGCCAUGGCUUCAGAGGGUGCAAGUUCCAAGCCUUUCAGGUUCUAGGUGGUGUUAAGCCUGCAGAUGCACCAAAGUCAAGAAUUAACGUUCAUGAACCUCCGCCUACAUUUCAGAAGAUGUAUGAAAAUGCCUGGAAAUCCAGGCAAAAGUUUGCUGUGGGGGGGAGGGGAGGGGGGGGCCCUCAUGGAUAACCUCUGCUAGGGCAGUGUCAAAGGGAAAUAUGGGGUUGGAGCUCCCACACAGAGUCCCCACUGGGGUACUGCCAAGCAGAGCUGUGAGAAAAGGGCCACCAUCCUCCAGACCCCAGAAUGGUAGAUCCACUGACAGCUUGCACUGUGUGCCUGGAAAAGCUGCAGACACUCAAUGCAGCCAGAAGGGGGGCUGUACCCUGCAAAGCCACAGGGGCGGGGCUGCCCAAGACCCUGGGAACCCACUUCUUGCAUCACCUAGAUGUGACACAUGGAGUCAAAGGAGGUCAUUUUGGAGCUUUAAGAUUUGCCUGCUGGGUUUUGGACUUGCAUGGGGCCUGUAGCUCUUUUGCUUUGGCCAAUUUCUCCCAUUUGAAACGAGUGUAUUUACCCAAUGCCUGUAUCCCUGUGUAUCUAGAAAAUAACUAACUUGCUUUUGAUUUUACAGGCUCAUAGGUGGAAGGGACUUGCCUUGUCUCAGAUGAGACUUUGGACUAUGGAAUUUUGAGUUAAUGCUGAAAUAAGAGUUUGGGGGACUUAGGGGAAGGCACGAUUGCUUUUGAAAUAUGAGGACAUGAGAUUUGGGAGGGGCCGGGGAAGAAUUAUAUGGUUUGGCUCUGUCCGCACCCAAAUCUCAUCUUGAAUUGUAACAAUUCCCAUGUGUCAAGGGUGGGGCCAGGUGGAGAUAACUGAAUCAUGGAGGCAGUUUCCCCCAUGCUGUUCUCAUGGUAGUGAAUAAGUCUCAUGAGGUCUGAUGGUUUUAUAAAUGGAUGUUCCCCUGCACAUGCUCUCUCCUGCCCACCAUGUCUGACUAAAUUUUGUAUUUUUACUAGAGACGGGCUUUCACUAUGUUGGCCAGGCUGGCCUCCAACUCCUGAUCUCGUGAUCCGUCCACCCCGACCUCCCAAAGUGCUAGGAUCAUAGGCAUAAGCCACCACACCCGGCCUCUUUUUUUUCUUUUUCUUUUUUUUAUCUGGAGACUGAGUUUUGCACUCGUUGCCCAGGCUGGAGUGCAAUGGUGCGAUCUCAGCUCACUGCAGUCUCCACCUCAGCAGGAGAGCAGGAAUCUUCAGUGAUCCACGGGCAAAUAUGCAGCCAUUGUGGGCACCUGUUCCUCCCGCGACCUUUGUGCCCACGUCUCUCCCUCCAGUACCUACUGCACGACCCCCCACGUCCGCCUCCUGCCAUUGCCAGCAGGUGCCUUGCGCGGGUACCUGGCUGUGCUUAUUCAUCCAUUAUGGUCGCUCUGUCACUGGUGCCAUUAUGUGCUCACAUGCCCACUCCCUCAGGUUUAGAAGUCGCGUUGCCCGGCAACAGAACAAUCUGCUGGCUUAGCCUUUGGCCAAGUUGGCAGCUGGAUGAGGACGCUCAGAGCCCAGCUCUUGAGAGUUCAAGUAUCCGACAGUUCCCCACUGCUCCCAGGAGCGGUUACCCGGGCACUCUGUGCCCCUCAUUCCUGUUUGGGCCAAGGCCGAGGACCUGCGAGUAGGGCUCAGUUGCCUGGAGCCCCUUCAGCCCAUCCCCCAGUUCACUUUGCUUGUGGGAUCUCCCCGUUGCUCCUGCCCCUGGACUGAGUGGCAGGCCAUCCUACAAACACCCGCACACUCGACAUCAGUGGUGUCAAGACAACUCUAAGAAGGUUUUCCGUGAUCCUGCAAGACCUGUGUUCCAUCCUGGUGAUUCUAUCUUCAAUUUCACUGCACAGGUACCACAGUAAGCCAGUGCUGUGUGCUCCGAGUUCCAGGGCAUCCCCCAGCUCAGCCACUACACUGAGCACAAGGACUCUGUGGGGCCCAGGAGCAGGUAGUCACCCCUUUGGGGUCCACAACACCCGGCUGUCCCCAGACUUGUGUCCAGGGAAGAUAGUGUUGAGGGCCCUCAAGGAGAGCGGGGCAGGGAUGCCUGAGCAGCACAAGGACCCCAGAGUCCAAGAAAAUCCUGAUGAUCAGAGAACGGUCCCCGAGGUCACCGGGGAUGCACGGUCUGCAUUUUGGCCCCUGCGGGACAAUGGAGGCCCCUCUCCCUUUGUGCCCAGGCCCGGGCCUCUGCAGACAGACCUCCACGCCCAGAGCUCAGAAAUCAGAUAUAACCACACAUCCCAGACAUCCUGGACGAGCUCGAGCACCAAACGAAAUGCCAUCUCCAGCUCCUACAGCUCCACGGGAGGCUUGCCGGGGCUAAAGCAGAGGAGGGGGCCAGCCUCAUCCCGCUGCCAGCUGACCCUCAGUUACUCAAAGACAGUGAGUGAGGACAGGCCUCAGGCUGUCUCUUUGGGUCACACACGGUGUGAAAAGGGGGCAGAUACAGCACCAGGGCAGACAAUCGCCCCAACGGGUGGCUCCCCCAGAUCCCAGGACUCUAGGCCCCGUAGACGCAAGAUUCCCCUGCUGCCACGCAGGCGAGGGGAGCCUUUGAUGCUGCCACCUCCCUUAGAGCUGGGGUACCGGGUCACGGCUGAAGACCUGCACCUGGAAAAAGAGACGGCAUUCCAGCGCAUCAACAGUGCACUGCACGUUGAGGACAAGGCCAUCCCGGACUGCAGACCCUCACGGCCUUCCCACACUUUGUCCUCACUUGCAACAGGGGCUUCGGGUGGGCCUCCCGUUUCUAAAGCACCCACUAUGGAUGCACAGCAGGACAGACCCAAGUCCCAAGACUGCCUGGGCCUAGUGGCCCCCCUAGCAUCUGCUGCAGAGGUCCCCGCUACAGCUCCCGUGUCUGGGAAGAAGCACAGACCACCAGGACCCCUGUUCUCCUCCUCAGAUCCCCUUCCUGCCAACUCUUCCCACUCCCGGGACUCAGCCCAGGUCACCUCGAUGAUUCCUGCCCCCUUCACAGCUGCAAGCAGGGAUGCCGGCAUGAGAAGAACAAGGUCGGCUCCUGCAGCUGCCGCAGCAGCCCCUCCCCCCUCCACAUUGAACCCCACGUCGGGGUCACUACUCAAUGCAGUGGAUGGAGGCCCCUCACAUUUCUUGGCCUCAGCCACAGCUGCAGCACGUGCCCAGAGGUCAGAAGUGAGAUAUAACCAGAGAUCCCAGACCUCCCGGACCAGAUCCUGCCUCAAACGAAAUGCCAGCUCCAGCUCCCACAGCUCUACGGAAGGCCUCCAGGAAGUAAAGCGGAGGAGGGGGCCAGCCUCAUCCCACUGCCAGCUGGCCCUCAGUUCCUCAAACACAGUGAGUGAGGACGGACCUCAGGCUGUCUCUUCGGGUCACCGCUGUGAAAACAAGGCAGGUACAGCACCAGGGCAGACACUUGCCCCCAGGGGUGGCUCCCCCAGAUCCCAGGCCUCUAGGCCCCACAUCAACACUGCACUGCACGUUGAGGACAAGGCCAUCUCGGACUGCAGACCCUCACGGCCUUCCCACACUUUGUCCUCACUUGCAACAGGGGCUUCGGGUGGGCCUCCCGUUUCUAAAGCACCCACUAUGGAUGCACAGCAGGACAGACCCAAGUCCCAAGACUCCCUGGGCCUACUGGCCCCCCUAGCAUCUGCUGCAGAGGUCCCCUCUACAGCUCCCGUGUCUGGGAAGAAGCACAGACCACCAGGACCCCUGUUCUCCUCCUCAGAUCCCCUUCCUGCCACCUCUUACCACUCCCGGGACACAGCACAGGUCACCUCGCUGAUUCCUGCCACCUUCACAGCUGCAAGCAGGGAUGCCGGCAUGAGAAGAACAAGGUCGGCUCCUGCAGCUGCCACAGCAGCCCCUCCCCCCUCCACAUUGAACAACACGUCGGGGUCACUACUCAAUGCAGUGGAUGGAGGCCCCUCACAUUUCUUGGCCUCAGCCACAGCUGCAGCACGUGCCCAGAGGUCAGAAGUGAGAUAUAACCAGAGAUCCCAGACCUCCCGGACCAGAUCCUGCCUCAAACGAAAUGCCAGCUCCAGCUCCAGCUCCCACAGCUCUACGGAAGGCCUCCAGGAACUAAAGCGGAGGAGGGGGCCAGCCUCAUCCCACUGCCAGCUGGCCCACAGUUCCUCAAACACAGUGAGUGAGGACGGACCUCAGGCUGUCUCUUCGGGUCACCGCUGUGAAAACAAGGCAGGUACAGCACCAGGGCAGACACUCGCCCCCAGGGGAGGCUCCCCCAGAUCCCAGGCCUCUAGGCCCCACAUCAACAGUGCACUGUACGUUGAGGACAAGGCCAUCUCGGACUGCAGACCCUCACGGCCUUCCCACACUUUGUCCUCACUUGCAACAGGGGCUUCGGGUGGGCCUCCCGUUUCUAAAGCACCCACUAUGGACGCACAGCAGGACAGACCCAAGUCCCAAGACUGCCUGGGCCUAGUGGCCCCCCUAGCAUCUGCUGCAGAGGUCCCCUCUACAGCUCCCGUGUCUGGGAAGAAGCACAGACCACCAGGACCCCUGUUCUCCUCCUCAGAUCCCCUUCCUGCCAACUCUUCCCACUCCCGGGACUCAGCCCAGGUCACCUCGCUGAUUCCUGCCACCUUCACAGCUGCAAGCAGGGAUGCCGGCAUGAGAAGAACAAGGCCUGGCACCUCGGCUCCUGCAGCUGCCGCAGCAGCCCUUCCCCCCUCCACAUUGAACCCCACGUCGGGGUCGCUACUCAAUGCAGUGGAUGGAGGCCCCUCACAUUUCUUGGCCUCAGCCACAGCUGCAGCACGUGCCCAGAGGUCAGAAGUGAGAUAUAACCAGAGAUCCCAGACCUCCCGGACCAGAUCCUGCCUCAAACGAAAUGCCAGCUCCAGCUCCCACAGCUCUACGGAAGGCCUCCAGGAACUAAAGCGGAGGAGGGGGCCAGCCUCAUCCCACUGCCAGCUGGCCCACAGUUCCUCAAACACAGUGAGUGAGGACGGACCUCAGGCUGUCUCUUCGGGUCACCGCUGUGAAAACAAGGCAGGUACAGCACCAGGGCAGACACUCGCCCCCAGGGGUGGCUCCCCCAGAUCCCAGGCCUCUAGGCCCCGCAUCAACAGUGCACUGCACGUUGAGGACAAGGCCAUCUCGGACUGCAGACCCUCACGGCCUUCCCACACUUUGUCCUCACUUGCAACAGGGGCUUCGGGUGGGCCUCCCGUUUCUAAAGCACCCACUAUGGAUGCACAGCAGGACAGACCCAAGUCCCAAGACUGCCUGGGCCUACUGGCCCCCCUAGCAUCUGCUGCAGAGGUCUCCUCUACAGCUCCCGUGUCUGGGAAGAAGCACAGACCACCAGGACCCCUGUUCUCCUCCUCAGAUCCCCUUCCUGCCACCUCUUCCCACUCCGGGGACUCAGCCCAGGACACCUCGCUGAUUCCUGCCCCCUUCACACCUGCAAGCAGGGAUGCCGGCAUCAGAAGAAUGUUUCGUGUUCGAAAUUGUUUGAGGGGUUUGGGUUUAUUUUUGUUGGUUUUUUCUUUUUUUUUUUUGCUUACGUGGGCAUCCUUCAGCUUUUAAUAAUCUGAAAAAUUCUAUUUACCCAUUGUCAAUGUGUAUAAAUUAAUCUCAGUCAAUUUUAUACAAUAAAAGGUGAACUUUUAUCCAUCAAACAAUAAUUUAACAAAAAAUGUACCGGAAGAAGAAUGUUCAUUACAAAUAUAGGAAACAUAAAUAUUACCAAAUAUUGGCAAGCACUAAAAUGUUCAGAAAUAUAAGUCUAUUACAGUUAUAGCUCUCUCAAGCAAAAAAACAGCAGAGAAAAACUUAGUUUUCCUGAGGGGCUAUUUAUUUACUUAGGGAUUUGUUAAAAGGUCAAAUGGGGUCACACAGAAUACUAAGAAGAGCUGUUCACCCAGGCCUCACUAAGAACUCUUCUUCAUGCAGUAGCUAUAUAGUAAUAUGACAACUGCUCCUACGACCCAAAGAGGAACUACAGCAACUACUCUUUAGCAUCUGUUGCUCCCAACUCUGCUUUGCAAUUAUAUGACUCAAGCAUUCUGGCUCCGUUAACUAUUACUGCUGUUACUCCCAAGUAAAUUCCCUCUAAAAAAUAAAAAUUUUUAAAGCUGUAA